GCAAUUACUCUCUUCCAUAUUGGUUAACAGUAGAAGGCUCAGUUUCUCUGCUCAUCACACGGCCUUCGGCACUGUAGCUUUGGGUGGUGGGCUGCAGAUUAAUUUUGUAACCACCUUAAGAAAAAUACGGAACUCUAACUCCUUGCCACUCAAGAAAUGUCCUCCCUUUCAGAAUAUGCCUUCCGCAUGUCUCGUCUCAGUGCCCGGCUAUUUGGUGAAGUCACCAGGCCUACUAAUUCCAAGUCUAUGAAAGUGGUGAAACUGUUUAGUGAACUGCCCUUGGCCAAGAAGAAGGAGACUUAUGAUUGGUAUCCAAAUCACCACACUUACGCUGAACUCAUGCAGACGCUCCGAUUUCUUGGACUCUACAGAGAUGAGCAUCAGGAUUUUAUGGAUGAGCAAAAACGACUAAAGAAGCUUCGUGGAAAGGAGAAACCAAAGAAAGGAGAAGGGAAAAGAGCAGCAAAAAGGAAAUAGUGUUGGUCCCUCAAGAGGGAGACUUUCUUCCUCAGUGGCGGAGAGAAGAAAGUGCAUUUAUUGUCUUUCCACCUAUUGGAGGAAUGUCAUCUUCCUAAAUGAAGUUUAUUUGGAGGAACACAGUCAUCUCCUUGGUGAAAUCUAAUCCGGUUACAUUGUGGCUGGUUUCUUGAACACAUUCUAACUGUGCAAAAUUAUCUUGGCCUUGGCCGUGUAAUGUGAGGUUUACCUGAUUCUCUAAUGAAAUAAAUACCUAAGUUAUUGUUUGAUGAUUUGUUUGGGGUGGGAUGGGAUGCUGGGGGAAUGGAGGGGAAACCUCAUUAAGUGAGCAUCCUAUAGUGUCCUCAUUUCUCCCUUCUUGCUUACUGACUCACCCAGCCCUAAACUUCUUUCAUCUUGGGCCUUUCAGCCACUGUCUCCACCACCAAGCUCACAAACUUUGUGUGUGUCUUCACCUACUCCUUUGAGAAAUCUAUUAAGAUGAAUUUGUAGAGUAAGUAUCUUUUAAAAGGAAGUAUUGAAUACCUGCUCUGUACAAGAUAUUGGGGCCCUGGUAAUACACGUGGUUAGCAAGAGAAAUACUCCCUACCUCAUGUAAGUUUCAGUCUUGUGGGAGGGACUAAUAUUACAUAAUUACAUACAAUUGUAUUACAUGCUACAAAGGAAAAAGCCAGACUUCUAUAAGAGCAUGGAUGGAUGGAUGAAUGCAGAGAGAGAUAGCCAGAAGCCCAAAUCACAUUAGGGAGUUUAAAGAAAGCUUCCCUAAAGAAAUGAUAUUUAAGCCAGGCGCUGUUGCUCACACCUGUAAUCCCACCACUUUGGGAGGCCGAGGUGGGUGGAUCACAAGGUCAAGAGAUCGAGACCAUUUUGGCCAACAUGGUGAAACCCCACCUACUAAAAAUGCAAAAAUUAGCUGGGCGUCGUGGCAUGCACCUGUAGUCUCAGCUACUCGGGAUGCUGAGGCAGGAGAAUCGCUUGAACCCGGGAGGCAAAGGUUGCAGUGAGUUGAGAUCACGCCACUGCACUCCAGCCUGGCAACAGAGCAAGACUACAUCUCAAAAAAAAAAUGAUAUUUAAGCUGAACCUUGAAGAAUAAAUAAGAGGUUGCCAAAAGGAAAAUGGUGAGAAAGGGGUUUGAGGCAGAGAGUACUAUUUGCAAAGCCCUAAGGUAUGAAGAAAUUGUCUGUUCAAGAAACACUGAGUUUGUUCAUGGUUGGCUGUAAGAAAACAGAGGCCAGAUCAUGAAGGGCUUUGGAAAUUCUGUGGAAAAGCUUGAACAUAACUAGAAGUUCUAUGAGGGAUGACUGUUGUAUAGAUUUGAGUAGCUCGCUGCUGGUUUUAUUGUAUUCCAGCAAUGAGUUUCCAAAGAAAUUGUGAAGGCUUGGCCGGGCACAGUGGCUCACGCCUGUAAUCCCAGCACUUUGGGAGGUCGAGGCGGGUGGAUCACGAGGUCAGGGGAUCGAGACCAUCCUGGCUAACAUGGUGAAACCCCGUCUCUACUAAAAAAUGCAAAAAAGUUAGCCGGGCGUGGUGGUGGGUGCCUGUAGUCCCAGCUACUUGGGAGGCUGAGGCAGGAGAAUGGCAGGGAGGCGGAGCUUGCAGUAAGCUGAGAUGGUGCCACUGCACUCCAGCCUGGGCAACAAAGCGAGACUCUGUCUCAAAAAAAAAAUUGUGAAGGCUUCUCUGAUUUUUUUUUCCAACAGUUGUUCUGAAUCUUUAGCAUGUCCAGUAAUUUUUUAAUAACUUUUUAUUAUUGUAGUAAAAACAUAAAAUUAAUGAUCUUAACCAUAUUUAAGUGUACAAUAGUGUCAAUAUUCAAACAUAUUAUUCAAAAAAUAAUCAAAAUAUAAAAGCAUUUUAGUGCGAUAGUAUUUAUUGGAGUAUGUAUAGCAGCUACUCCAGCCACAGUUUUCUUUCUCUGUAACACUCAAUGAUUCCUGAAGUAGAAAGAUUCCCAGUACAUAUGUUUAAAUGAAUGCUAUUUUUAAAGAUACCUAAUCCAGAUGGUAUGGCUAGGGCCUAUUUUAUAGCCUGUUUAAAAAAAUAAAAUAAAAUAAAAUUGGGUGGUUUGUAUGUGGUAGAAGUGAAUUCCAGCAAAAGGAGAAUUCAUUCAUUUAGACCUUUUUUUUUGUUUGAGACGGAGUCUCACUCUCACCAGCUGGAGUGCAGUGGCGCAAUCUCAGCUCACUGCAAGCUCCACCUCCCGGGUUCACGCCAUUCUCCUGCCUCAGCCUCCCAAGUAGCUGGGACUACAGGCGCCCACCACCACGCCCGGCUAAUAUUUUGUAUUUUUAGUAGAGAAGGUGUCUCACUGUGUUAGCCAGGAUGGUCUCAACCUCUUGACCUCCUGAUCCACCCACCUCAGACUCCCAAAGUGCUGGAAUUACAGGCAUGAGCCACCACACCCAGCCCAUUUAGAACUUUUUACUGAGCACCUGCCAUGUGCUCGACACGUGAUAGUUGUAGAGGAUACAGAGACAAAUAGACUUAGUCCCUAAGACUGUGUGAAUGAGCAUGUGUGUAUUACAAAGUAUUGGCAAGAUCUCAGAAACGUGCUUAGAAAAGUGCAGAUGCACUGUUAUUCUUGGCCAAUGCAGCUGAGCCAGGUGUAGGUGGAUGACUACCCCAGGAUGUUGAGCUGAGAAACAGGAUCUCAGCCUGAACCCAAUGUAGCUCAGCAGAUGUUUGAAUUAUGUGAUCUCCAGCUUUUGGGAAAGAUCUGAAUGUAAGAGGAACUUAAGAGAAUUAGCAUGAUAUUUUAAAGAGAAUAACUGCAUUACAUUCUAACAGCAGACCUGAGUCGGAAAACAAGUAAAGAAUCGAUGUAUUGGUUUGCCGAUGGAAGAGCUUCAGUGAGAUCUCAGACCCUGACCCUGCAGUGAGCCUUGGCAAUGAUUGACAGGGAAGUUUGUAGAUAACGCAGAAGUAGAUUAGUGUGCCACUGCUCCAGGCUGAAAAUCAGAAAUGAAAGCUAAAAUACAUUUGUACAUAAGCUAUACCUUCAAUUGAUAGAGCAAGCUGUGUGACUCAAAACAGCCUGUACAGAAGUACGAUGGACCAGCUGGAAGGUAUCAAUAGAAGAUAAGGAAAAGUUAACUCUUGACACCAGGGAAGUCAACAAAUUUCAGGACAACAGUGACCAAUGGUUAAGAUGGUGACUAAGUGUAAUCAGAAAAAAAUCUUUAACUCCAAGUUUAGACUAGCCAGUUUGUUUAAUUGGAUUUCUCUGGUCAAAACCUAAACUAUUGGUGCUUUCUAACCUGUGGGGAUCAGUGUGCAUAGACCAUUUUGCCCUCGAUUUCAGCAUAACAUAGUAAAAAGACUGGGUUUUAGAUUCAAAAGUCAUGGGUUUGUGAUACAGUGUACUUACUGAUUAUGUGACGUCAGUUACUUCUCUGAACCUCUUUCCUUCUCUAUAAAAUCAUAAUGCUUCACUGGAUUAAUGAAAUAAGAUAUUUGUGAAAAGAACUCUGUAAAUUAUAAAAAGUUAAAAACUUUUACAUAUAGCACAUUAUGUGACUAGUAAGUACUGCUGUGUCUUACUAGCGCAAUUUUCUGUGGCAGCAUUGACACGUAUCUCCUAAAAAUAUAAAGUUCCCCACGUUUACAAGCAGCAUGAUAGGUUCAGGAAGAGGAGGUAGAUGAGAGGUAACAUCUUAUUAUUUAUGUAAUUAUGGGCUCCAUAAGUUUAUUUUUUAAGCACCAUAUAUGUGUGUGUUUCAAAAUAAACAUAAGGCAUCAUAUAUUUAAACAUAUAUAACCAUAAUGCUUGUAUUUAUAAAUCAUUUUCCAAGAAAGAAUAAAUCAAAAUUUGAAAUUC